CCUGGCCUGAAGCAGUCCUCCCGACCUGUCCUCUCAAAGUGCUGGCAUUGCAGGUGUGAGCCAGAGUUUUACAGUCAGAUCAUGGAGAUCUGAAAUGUUGCCCCAUCUCACCGAAGACCGAGUGCCCGGGAGCCCCCCUAGGAGGGUCAGAACCUGCCCGGGAGCCCCCUAGGAGGGUCAGAACCUGCCCGGGAGCCCCCCUAGGAGGGCCGGCACCUGCCUGCCCGGGAGCCCCCCUAGGAGGGCCGGCACCUGCCUGCCCGGGAGCCCCCCUAGGAGGGCCGGCACCUGCCUGCCCGGGAGCCCCCCUAGGAGGGUCAGAACCUGCCUGGUUAGCUCAGAUGCCCCCGUGGAGACAGCGUGAGGGCGGCAGGGAGCUGGAAACCUUCCCAGGUUCCCAAUUUUGAGAUUUCCUAAGCUGCCUGUGGUCCAGCUGGGAGGAAGUGUCUGGUCCUGAUGUGCGUCGGUGACCACAGACAAAACAGGAUUUGCUCCUGCGCCAACGUUGGCUUUUGAGCAGCGGGAUAGGUGGGCCUGGUGGUAGGUGCUUCGGCAGCCGGGCAGCCGCAGGGACUUCCUCCCUCGGGAUUAAACCUGAGUCGGGAGUUGGAGGGCAACAGUUAUUCACAUUCAAAACCAGAUCUUAAGUGCAAAUUAACGUUUUUUGGAUUCUUGAGCAAAAUGUUUUCUACAUUAUGAUGGGAUUUUCUUUUUUAUAAGUGCUUCUAGAACAUCUCUGGAAGCUGGGUUAGACGCACAGGGCUUAGUCGGCUUUGGGGAGAGACAGUAGUUGUAAAGGCCACACCGGACGCCGUGUGCACCUCCCAAGGUUUCCCAUGUGAGACCAUGUGGCCUGCAUGCUGCGUUCCAUCAGCACUGGGCUGUGCGACAGAUGUGUUUCCAGGCGAGGUUGCUGCAGAGGGGAAGAGGGGGACGUGUUUCCAGGCGACGUCGCUGCAGAGAGGAAGAGGGGGACGCGUUUCCAGGUGACGUCGCUGCAGAGAGGAAGAGGGGGACACGUUUCCAGGCGACGUCGCUGCAGAGAGGAAGAGGGGGACGCGUUUCCAGGCGACGUCGCUGCAGAGAGGAAGAGGGGGACACGUUUCCAGGUGACGUCGCUGCAGAGAGGAAGGAGGGUCGCGUUUCCAGGCGAGGUCGCUGCAGAGGGGAAGAGGGGGACGCCUUUCCAGGUGACUUCGCUGCAGAGAGGAAGAGGGGGACGCCUUUCCAGGUGACUUCGCUGCAGAGAGGAAGAGGCAGACGCAUUUCCAGGCGAGGUCACUGCAAAGAGGAAGAGGGGGAUGCGUUUCCAGGUGACAUCGCUACAGACAGGAAGAGGGGGAUGCGUUUCCGGGAGACGUCGCUGCAGAGGGGAAGAGGUGGAUGCGUUUCCAGGCAAGGUCGCUGCAGAGAGGAAGAGGGGGUCGCAUUUCCAGGCAGCAUGGCUGCAGAGAGGAAGAGGAGGACGUGUUUCCAGGCGACGUUGCUGCAGAGAGGAAGAGGAGGACGCGUUUCCAGGCGAUGUCGUUGCAGAGGGCAAGAGGGGAACGCGUUUCCAGGUGACGUCGCUGCAGAGGGGAAGAGGCGGAUGCGUUUCCAGGUGACAUUGCUGCAGAGAGGAAGAGGAAGAUGCUUUUCCAGGCGACGUUGCUGCAGAGAGGAAGAGGGUGGGACGCAUUUCCAGGAGACGUCGCUGAAGAGGGGAAGAGGGAGGCCCCUCCAGCAGGGCCACCUAGAUGUUUGCUUUGCCCCGCGUGGAGUCAUAUUCCAGGAACCCCCGAACCCACCUGCAGCUUGAUUCUGCUCCUCAGGGCCAGAGGUUCUAGUUUAUGGGAGGAGUGUUUUCUCACUGGAAACAUGGAGCCCACACACACUUCUACGCUGGAAGCCGUGAUGUGUGUCAGGAACGUGUUCUGAUGUUGGUGUGCAAAAUCAGUAUUGUGCCUUUGUCCCCUCUGACCCCCAUCACGGCAGUUCUGAGGCUUGUGGGGCACCCCAGCUCCUCUCCCUCUGCACAGGCCACUGUUCCCAGAACUCGAGGGUUCCCUGACACCAAGAUGACAUGUGGCACAGACCUGGAAUCACGAGGAAAUGCCCGUCCUCCUCCCACGGGCAGACAGGUCGAGUGUGUUUCCAGAGACCGGGCCGUCCGUGGGGCAGUAGCGCCUGGAUGACGUCUGCUUUCGCCUGGAGCCCUGGCUGCAAGGGGCGGUGCCGGGCAAGGGCCACCCCAGGGGUCUGGGAGUGCAGUGUCGGGCCUGUGGAGGUGGAGAGCAGGGAUCAGCCUCUUUUUGUGGAUGAGGAAAUGGAGACACGUGGAAACUUCUGGUAAGAAGCUGUCAAGCCUCCAGGUUUCGGUUCUGGACAGGUGCGGGGCAGGUAUUGGAGCACUUUGGGCUCUGAGGUCCACGUGGCCCAGCGGCCUCCAGGAGUCAGCUGCAAGGCGGAGUCCCUGUCCACAAGCUGCGUUGCAGGCACAGAGACCAGGAGAGGGCUGUGAAGCAACUCUGUGUUUACUGGGCUGAAGCAGCAGCUCUUGGCAGUGCCGCCACCAUGGGCUGUGUCCUGUCCCCGUGGCGACAUCACAGCUGAGCGCGAAGCUGGAAGCUUGGGCACGUCUUGGUGCUGGGUCUUCUCCGACCCCGAGGGCCAAGGGUGCUCUGUAGCUCCAGGCGUCAGAGUCUGAGCAUCCUUUGUUUUGGCAACAUCCAGGACAGGAGUCUUUGGAGAGUAACACAUCCUUAUUUUGAAAGAUCCCUUUAGGUGAUUUGAGAAACCGCUGUAUUUGUUGUAGCUCCAAGUAUUACCCGUGAAUCACCUAGGCUGCUCUUCAGUGAACAUCCAGAAUGCCGUCAGUUCUUGUGAAACCCCCAAGUUUCCCGUAGGUCCAAGCUGAGAAGAUUGAGUGAACUCUGAGAGCUGAGCCGGGCCGUCUUGGCACCACUAGAAACGGAAUCAGUUCCAUGACUGAUCUGUGCCCCACCCCACAUUAACUUGUGCAAUAUGACAUUUCUGGUUUUGGUUUUUGUUUUAUAAGCCAUCCAUGGCAAGUGCAGUCGGAGGCCCCCCACUGCCAAAACUUCCUGUGAGUAAUAAUGACAGAUGGGCCCUGACCCUGGAGACGUCUGAGAAGGUGUUUGGGGUCCGAGAAGAGUCCGCGUGUGCAGUGACUGGAACCUGUCCCUGGUGUGAACUUGGGGAUGAGUGGGUGACGGGGGUGGUGGGGGCCUGGGGCACUUCCCCGCCCUCCGGACCACACUGUUGCUCUCCAGCCACGAGAAGAUGCAGCGGCCCCCGGCUGCAGCAGCUACUGUCCCGGAGGGCAGGGGAGUGAGGGAGAGGGAGGGUGUACGGCAUGGGGCCUGCUGCCUGGGGCGCUGGGAUCCCACAGCGAGGCCCUGUUCCCACUGCCCAGGGGCACUGAGAUCCCACAGGGAGGCCCGGUUCCCACUGAGCUUGGGUUCCCAACGGGCUCCUUUUGCUUCCCAAGCACCCUCUCCCACCCUUGAGCUGCAAGGAAUGUUUCAGAGCCAUGGAAGGUGCUUUCUCCCAUCUGUAGUUUUUCUGGGAGGGAGAAAGGCUGACAUCGGGGGCUUUGUAGAAAGCGUGCUCUGGCCCACACGUUAACAUUUGGGAGGAGGCCUACAGGGAGCUG